UCGCAGCUAUUUGGGCAGCUUGGAAUGGGAACUGGUGGUCUUCCUAGACCACAGGUAAUGAGGGGUGGCGUGGAGGAGGCAGCCGUGCCAGGCAGGAAGAUCAUCCUGGGAUCUGCGAUGUGUGCAUCGGAAGCACCCAGAGAGAAUAGAAGCUGCCAGAAAAAUGCAAGGAAACCCAGAAACUCGGAGAGCACAAACGAAUCACAGUUUUUAUUGUGUGAAUUUUCACUAAAUAUCCUACAAUGAAUAUUCGUCAUAAGAAAAAGUCAUUUUUAAUGUCAUGAUUUCCUGGAAAUAUAGAAAGAAAGAAAAACAGAAAAGGCACAACUGCCCCCGAGCACAGCAGCAGAAUCUUGGUGGUGGGCGCUCCCCUGCCACGCCCGGGGAUGCUCCUGCUUCAGGAGUUCACUUGGCUCAGUUAUGGCAGCAGGUUCUGAUGCUGCAGAGCUCAGAGCAGAAAGGCUAAGGACGCCUGCUUAGGGCCCCUACUGUGUGUGUGCAUGUCUGUGUGCACGCAUGUGUAUGUGUAGGUCUGUGUGCAGGGCUGUGUGCAUGACUGCACGUAUGUGGAUGGGUGCACGACUGUGUACCUGUGUGUGUAUAUGUGUGGGUGGGUGCGCCUGAUUGUGUGUGUGUGUGCGUGUGUGUCUCACGCCAGAUUGGUUCUGCUCAGGUGCUCUGCAUCAUUUCUGCAAUCUGAUUUCUCCAAGUCUCAAAGGUCGAAUGUGCACCAUCAACAGCACUGAGAGCCUCUUAGAAAGGCAAAGUCUCCCCAGACCGGAUGCACUCCCAGCUUCCGUGCCUGGAAUUAGCGUAUUUCCUGCAACACCAGGCCGGGCAGAGCUAGGCAAAGUCACCCAGGAUCUGGAGUUGCCAGAAUGCAGCUUCGGCCACUGACAGCAUCAUCAUGGCCACAUAAAAAAUCCCCCAAAUAAAUUUCCUUGGAAGAAGUAAAUAAGUUCUUUGUACUUAAGUUUGGAGGUGACCAGUCCUAACUGGUAACUGAAUUCCUUGUGAUGUCUUACAAAUCCUUUGCUUUCUAAUUCUAUAAAUUAUGUGUGCUUUUCCCCGGAGAUCUUCUGAGAAUUUCCUUUAGAGAGCAUUUGACUCGGAGGCCAUCGGCAUCAGAUCAGCCCAGGACACUUCAAUGGUGAAUUGUGUGAUAAGCAACAAAAUCUCAGUAAAGCUAAAACAUCAGCACAGAAAAGACCUUAAAGAAACCGCCUCCUCAGCCACGGAGCCGGCACAACGGGAAAGAAACCACCUCCUCGGCCACAGAGCCGGCGCGGCCGGAAAGAAACCGCCUCCUCAGCCAUGGAGCCGGCGCGGCCGGAAAGAAACCGCCUCCUCAGCCACGGAGCCGGCAGAACCCGAAAGAAACCGCCUCCUCAGCCACGGAGCCGGCAGAACCAGAAAGAAACCGCCUCCUCAGCCACGGAGCCGGCAGAACCCGAAAGAAACCGCCUCCUCAGCCAUGGAGCCGGCGCGGCCGGAAAGAAACCGCCUCCUCAGCCAUGGAGCCGGCGCGGCCGGAAAGAAACCGCCUCCUCAGCCAUGGAGCCGGCGCGGCCGGAAAGAAACCGCCUCCUCAGCCACGGAGCCGGCAGAACCCAAAAGAAACCGCCUCCUCAGCCACGGAGCCGGCGCGGCCGGAAAGAAACCGCCUCCUCAGCCACGGAGCCAGCGCGGCCGGAAAGAAACCGCCUCCUCAGCCACGGAGCCGGCAGAACCCGAAAGAAACCGCCUCCUCGGCCACGGAGCCAGCGCGGCCGGAAAGAAACCGCCUCCUCAGCCACGGAGCCGGCAGAACCCGAAAGAAACCGCCUCCUCGGCCACGGAGCCGGCAGAACCCGAAAGAAACCGCCUCCUCAGCCACGGAGCCGGCAGAACCCGAAAGAAACCGCCUCCUCAGCCACGGAGCCAGCGCGGCCGGAAAGAAACCGCCUCCUCAGCCACGGAGCCGGCAGAACCCGAAAGAAACCGCCUCCUCGGCCACGGAGCCGGCAGAACCCGAAAGAAACCGCCUCCUCGGCCACGGAGCCGGCAGAACCCGAAAGAAACCGCCUCCUCGGCCACGGAGCCGGCAGAACCCGAAAGAAACCGCCUCCUCGGCCACGGAGCCGGCAGAACCGGAAAGAAACCGCCUCCUCGGCCACGGAGCCGGCACAACGGGAAAGAAACCGCCUCCUCAGCCACGGAGCUGGCACAACUGGAAAGCAACUCUCCGAGCUGAAAAGCAAUGGGUUUGCAAAGAGUGGGAAAACACACAGAAGGCGGGUCAUGCAAAACGUCCUCCCGUGUCUGUAAAUGGCAGUUGCCCGCCACGAUGUCCAGAUGCACCGGGGAGUCUGGCCACGCCAAGGGAGAGACCAGAGAGGGCGACUAGCACAGCGUUCACAUCUGGUGGCUCUGUCCCCCCAGACACUCCGCACCGAAGCCUGGGGCAGAGGAGAAACCUCGUGCCUGCACACAGAAGGUGUCUCCACAAGGAGCCGUCUCUACAGCGUGACUGUGGAAAGCAGGCCUCGGGACCCUGGGACCAGCACCAAGAAUGCCAGACCUGGUUCUCCGAGGCUGCGGCAUUCCUCCCACGUCUGCCUCUAGGGGCCACGCAAGGGAGCUGAGACACGGGAGUUACAGAGCACUCAGCUUCCCCACAAGAACUGGCUCUGGACACUAGACAAGGUGCAAAGAUGACUCGUGCAGUUCUGCCCUGUAAGAAUCCACAGUUGAAGUAAGAAGCAAGAGAAAUGGAACAGACGAUGAGACAAAGCAGACAGCGGUGACAGCAUCCCACCACACGGCUGCCCUGCUGGAGAAUUCACGGGGAAGUCCAGGAUGUGGCCGGCCCGUGUGCAGACCAGGAGCUCACUGACCGAUCAACACAUCAGGCAGGGGGUUGUCAACCGUGGCCUCGCCUGAGGGUCCCCCAGGGGCUAAGGACCCAGAUACUCAGGACACAGGCCAGCCGGACCCCGCACAUCAGUCGCUGGAGGGGGUGGAUGUUUGAAGCUCCCCAGGGUUUAGACUUUGGAGAAACCAAAACAGAAAGACCUGCCUGGAGCUCCCACACGGACCCCUCCCUAGAGCCCCAGAUUCUACUGGCCCCCACUGGAACAGGGGAGGAAGCAGAGGAAGAAGGUACAUGCAGCCUCCAGAAAAAUGAUCAGGAUGAUUCCAGACUCACCCGAUAGGGCCAUCAGGGCAGGCGAUUAGCCUUGAUUCCACCUGGGGAGAGGGGCCUCCCCAACCACACAGCCCUGUUGGGGGAAGGAGCUGCUGGGACCUGCCAAGGGAAUGGGCCUCCCCUGGAGCUCUAAGAGUCAAAAGCUGAGGCUUUUUUGCAUAAAAGCAGGGCAGGAGGAAUUGGGGGUGUGGUGGCCGAGGCACUACUGAGUUCAAAAGAAGCUCGUUGAGGGCAGGGACCUUCGCCCCAGUUCUCACAGGAGGCACUCCCUGAACAAAAGCUGCAGGAGGACCAUACAGGCCAAACUGCCAAACUCAGACCAGCACCUGCUGGGCCGAGGCCACGGGGACGCCUGGUCUUCUCCUACCCAUACCCACCACGGCCGCUGGGCAGAGGACAUGGGGGACCCACGGGGGCCUGACUGCUGGGAAUACCCAUUGGCUUGAGCAGAUGUGAGUCAACAAGACUCAGACAAUGACGUGGGCUCUAAGAAGGUGGCAGUUACGUGAACUGUGAAGCUCAGUUCCUCCCGUUUGUUCAGAGCCUCCGCAUCCUGGCCCCAGCUCAGGUGGGAGUCGUUGCUGAGGCACCCGUGUGUGCACGUGGCCUGGCUCUCAGCUCUCAGGGAUCAGUAGUGCUGGCAGCAAAACAUGACCCUUCCUGUAACAAAAUGCCCAUGAAAUGGAGCAGGGGAUGAAUAACGUAAGCCGAGCCAUGAGGGAGCGGGAGGGGCCGCCCCGCCUGUCUGUACAGGGUGUGGGGUGAGGGCAGGAAGGGGACAGGAGGUGCCCCCAGAGACAUGAAUUUUUAAAAAUUAAACACACUCCUUGCACUUUGCUAGAAGGCCUCUGUCACCAUGUGACCGGGGACCUCUUCAGGGCUCCCAGCAGGAAAGGCAGAAUUACACCCCCCGGGAAGCCUGAAGCCCACCCUCUCGCAGCCCUGAGCCGGGCAACGGCGGCUCACCAGCACCUCCUGUUCUAGGCGGCAUUUUUCUAAAGUGCAGAGUGCAGCAGCCUCUGCAUCACCCCACUGCAGGGAGAGAGCCACGCCCUUUGCAGUUGUGAAACCAGACCCGCUGGACAGUUCGCCUCCAAGCACACAGUGCAUAUUGGAUACUGACAGGCCAGGGUGGCAGUGGGGCUCCUGGGACCCACGUGACAGGACAAGAGCUGAGGCUCAGCCAGUCGCCCCCACAAGGCCAGCCGAAGAAUGCCAGGGACCGAGAGCUGAGGCUCAGUGAGCCAUCCCACCCAUGCCAGCGGGAGAAUGCCAGGUACAUCGCUCUCCAUGCUGUCGUCCUCAAACCCCAGCACAAUGCCUCACCCUUGGUAACAUUCAGCCUUCAGCUCAUUUGUCUUGCAAAUAAAAAGGUUGAACUUGGAAGAA